GCCCGCCCACCUACCUCCCCGCCGCUCCAGAGGGGGCUCGCAGAGCUGAGGACGCGCGCAGCGCUGCUCAAGGUCUCUCUCUCUCAGCACCCUCGCCGGCCGGCGUCUGACGCGGGUGCCAGGGUCUCCGGGCACCUUUCAGUGUCCAUUCCCUCAGCCAGCCAGGACUCCGCAACCCAGCAGUUGCCGCUGCGGCCACAGCCCGAGGGGACCUGCGGACAGGACGCCGGCAGGAGGAGGGGUGCGCAGCGCCCGCGCAGAGCGUCUCCCUCGCUACGCAGCGAGACCCGGGCCUCCCGGCCCCAGGAGCCCCCAGCUGCCUCGCCAGGUGUGUGGGACUGAAGUUCUUGGAGAAGGGAGUCCAACUCUUCAAGGUGAACUAUGACCACUUUACUCUGGGUUUUCGUGACUCUGAGGGUCAUCACUGCAGCUGUCACUGUAGAAACUUCAGACCAUGACAACUCGCUGAGUGUCAGCAUCCCCCAACCGUCCCCGCUGAGGGUCCUCCUGGGGACCUCCCUCACCAUCCCCUGCUAUUUCAUCGACCCCAUGCACCCUGUGACCACCGCCCCUUCUACCGCCCCACUGGCCCCAAGAAUCAAGUGGAGCCGUGUGUCCAAGGAGAAGGAGGUAGUGCUGCUGGUGGCCACUGAAGGGCGCGUGCGGGUCAACAGUGCCUAUCAGGACAAGGUCUCACUGCCCAACUACCCGGCCAUCCCCAGUGACGCCACCUUGGAAGUCCAGAGCCUGCGCUCCAAUGACUCUGGGGUCUACCGCUGCGAGGUGAUGCAUGGCAUCGAGGACAGCGAGGCCACCCUGGAAGUCGUGGUGAAAGGCAUCGUGUUCCAUUACAGAGCCAUCUCUACACGCUACACCCUCGACUUUGACAGGGCGCAGCGGGCCUGCCUGCAGAACAGUGCCAUCAUUGCCACGCCUGAGCAGCUGCAGGCCGCCUACGAAGACGGCUUCCACCAGUGUGACGCCGGCUGGCUGGCUGACCAGACUGUCAGAUACCCCAUCCACACUCCCCGGGAAGGCUGCUAUGGAGACAAGGAUGAGUUUCCUGGUGUGAGGACGUAUGGCAUCCGAGACACCAACGAGACCUAUGAUGUGUACUGCUUCGCCGAGGAGAUGGAGGGUGAGGUCUUUUAUGCAACAUCUCCAGAGAAGUUCACCUUCCAGGAAGCAGCCAAUGAGUGCCGGCGGCUGGGUGCCCGGCUGGCCACCACGGGCCAGCUCUACCUGGCCUGGCAGGCUGGCAUGGACAUGUGCAGCGCCGGCUGGCUGGCCGACCGCAGCGUGCGCUACCCCAUCUCCAAGGCCCGGCCCAACUGCGGUGGCAACCUCCUGGGCGUGAGGACCGUCUACGUGCAUGCCAACCAGACGGGCUACCCCGACCCCUCAUCCCGCUACGACGCCAUCUGCUACACAGGUGAAGACUUUGUGGACAUCCCAGAAAACUUCUUUGGAGUGGGGGGUGAGGAGGACAUCACCGUCCAGACAGUGACCUGGCCUGACAUGGAGCUGCCACUGCCUCGAAACAUCACUGAGGGUGAAGCCCGAGGCAGCGUGAUCCUUACCGUAAAGCCCAUCUUCGAGGUCUCCCCCAGUCCCCUGGAACCCGAGGAGCCCUUCACGUUUGCCCCUGAAAUAGGGGCCACUGCCUUCGCUGAGGUUGAGAAUGAGACUGGAGAGGCCACCAGGCCCUGGGGCUUUCCCACACCUGGCCUGGGCCCUGCCACGGCAUUCACCAGUGAGGACCUCGUCGUGCAGGUGACCGCUGUCCCUGGGCAGCCGCAUUUGCCAGGGGGGGUCGUCUUCCACUACCGCCCGGGACCCACCCGCUACUCGCUGACCUUUGAGGAGGCACAGCAGGCCUGCCUGCGCACGGGGGCGGUCAUUGCCUCGCCGGAGCAGCUCCAGGCCGCCUACGAAGCAGGCUAUGAGCAGUGUGACGCCGGCUGGCUGCGGGACCAGACCGUCAGAUACCCCAUUGUGAGCCCCCGGACCCCAUGCGUGGGUGACAAGGACAGCAGCCCAGGGGUCAGGACCUAUGGCGUGCGCCCAUCAACAGAGACCUACGAUGUCUACUGCUUUGUAGACAGACUUGAGGGGGAGGUGUUCUUCGCCACACGCCUUGAGCAGUUCACCUUCCAGGAAGCACUGGAGUUCUGUGAAUCUCACAAUGCUACGCUGGCCACCACGGGCCAGCUCUACGCCGCCUGGAGCCGCGGCCUGGACAAGUGCUAUGCCGGCUGGCUGGCCGACGGCAGCCUCCGCUACCCCAUCGUCACCCCAAGGCCUGCCUGCGGUGGGGACAAGCCAGGCGUGAGAACGGUCUACCUCUACCCUAACCAGACGGGCCUCCCAGACCCACUGUCCCGGCACCAUGCCUUCUGCUUCCGAGGCAUUUCAGCGGUUCCUUCUCCAGGAGAAGAAGAGGGUGGCACACCCACAUCACCCUCUGGUGUGGAGGAGUGGAUCGUGACCCAAGUGGUUCCUGGUGUGGCUGCUGUCCCCGUAGAAGAGGAGACAACUGCUGUACCCUCAGGGGAGACUACUGCCAUCCUAGAGUUCACCACCGAGCCAGAAAACCAGACAGAAUGGGAACCAGCCUAUACCCCAGUGGGCACAUCCCCGCUGCCAGGGAUCCUUCCUACUUGGCCUCCCACUGGCGCAGCAACAGAGGAAAGUACAGAAGGCCCUUCUGCAACUGAAGUGCCCUCUGCCUCAGAGGAACCAUCCCCCUCAGAGGUGCCAUUCCCCUCAGAGGAGCCAUCCCCCUCAGAGGAACCAUUCCCCUCAGUGAGGCCAUUCCCCUCAGUGGAGCUGUUCCCCUCAGAGGAGCCAUUCCCCUCCAAGGAGCCAUCCCCCUCAGAGGAACCAUCAGCCUCGGAAGAGCCGUAUACACCUUCACCCCCCGUGCCCAGCUGGACUGAGCUGCCCAGCUCUGGGGAGGAAUCUGGGGCCCCUGAUGUCAGUGGUGACUUCACAGGCAGUGGAGAUGUUUCAGGACACCUUGACUUCAGUGGGCAGCUGUCAGGGGACAGGGCAAGUGGACUGCCCUCUGGAGACCUGGACUCCAGUGGUCUUACUUCCACAGUGGGCUCAGGCCUGCCUGUGGAAAGUGGACUACCCUCAGGGGAUGAAGAGAGAAUUGAGUGGCCCAGCACUCCUACGGUUGGUGAACUGCCCUCUGGAGCUGAGAUCCUAGAGGGCUCUGCCUCUGGAGUUGGGGAUCUCAGUGGACUUCCUUCUGGAGAAGUUCUAGAGACCUCUGCCUCUGGAGUAGGAGACCUCAGUGGGCUUCCUUCUGGAGAAGUUCUAGAGACCACUGCCCCUGGAGUAGAGGACAUCAGCGGGCUUCCUUCUGGAGAAGUUCUAGAGACCACUGCCCCUGGAGUAGAGGACAUCAGCGGGCUUCCUUCUGGAGAAGUUCUAGAGACCACUGCCCCUGGAGUAGAGGACAUCAGCGGGCUUCCUUCUGGAGAAGUUCUAGAGACCACUGCCCCUGGAGUAGAGGACAUCAGCGGGCUUCCUUCUGGAGAAGUUCUAGAGACCACUGCCCCUGGAGUAGAGGACAUCAGCGGGCUUCCUUCUGGAGAAGUUCUAGAGACCACUGCCCCUGGAGUAGAGGACAUCAGCGGGCUUCCUUCUGGAGAAGUUCUAGAGACCGCUGCCCCUGGAGUAGAGGACAUCAGCGGGCUUCCUUCUGGAGAAGUUCUAGAGACCGCUGCCCCUGGAGUAGAGGACAUCAGCGGGCUUCCUUCUGGAGAAGUUCUAGAGACCGCUGCCCCUGGAGUAGAGGACAUCAGCGGGCUUCCUUCUGGAGAAGUUCUAGAGACCGCUGCCCCUGGAGUAGAGGACAUCAGCGGGCUUCCUUCUGGAGAAGUUCUAGAGACCGCUGCCCCUGGAGUAGAGGACAUCAGCGGGCUUCCUUCUGGAGAAGUUCUAGAGACCGCUGCCCCUGGAGUAGAGGACAUCAGCGGGCUUCCUUCUGGAGAAGUUCUAGAGACCGCUGCCCCUGGAGUAGAGGACAUCAGCGGGCUUCCUUCUGGAGAAGUUCUAGAGACUGCUGCCCCUGGAGUAGAGGACAUCAGCGGGCUUCCUUCUGGAGAAGUUCUAGAGACUGCUGCCCCUGGAGUAGAGGACAUCAGCGGGCUUCCUUCUGGAGAAGUUCUAGAGACUGCUGCCCCUGGAGUAGAGGACAUCAGCGGGCUUCCUUCUGGAGAAGUUCUAGAGACUGCUGCCCCUGGAGUAGAGGACAUCAGCGGGCUUCCUUCUGGAGAAGUUCUAGAGACUGCUGCCCCUGGAGUAGAGGACAUCAGCGGGCUUCCUUCUGGAGAAGUUCUAGAGACUGCUGCCCCUGGAGUAGAGGACAUCAGCGGGCUUCCUUCUGGAGAAGUUCUAGAGACUGCUGCCCCUGGAGUAGAGGACAUCAGCGGGCUUCCUUCUGGAGAAGUUCUAGAGACUGCUGCCCCUGGAGUAGAGGACAUCAGCGGGCUUCCUUCUGGAGAAGUUCUAGAGACUGCUGCCCCUGGAGUAGAGGACAUCAGCGGGCUUCCUUCUGGAGAAGUUCUAGAGACUACUGCCCCUGGAGUAGAGGAGAUCAGCGGGCUUCCUUCUGGAGAAGUUCUAGAGACUACUGCCCCUGGAGUAGAUGAGAUCAGUGGGCUUCCUUCUGGAGAAGUUCUAGAGACUACUGCCCCUGGAGUAGAGGAGAUCAGCGGGCUUCCUUCUGGAGAAGUUCUAGAGACUUCUACCUCUGCGGUAGGGGACCUCAGUGGACUUCCUUCUGGAGGAGAAGUUCUAGAGAUUUCUGUCUCUGGAGUAGAGGACAUCAGUGGGCUUCCUUCUGGAGAGGUUGUAGAGACUUCUGCCUCUGGAAUAGAGGAUGUCAGUGAACUUCCUUCAGGAGAAGGUCUAGAGACCUCUGCUUCUGGAGUAGAGGACCUCAGCAGGCUCCCUUCUGGAGAAGAAGUUCUAGAGAUUUCUGCCUCUGGAUUUGGGGACCUCAGUGGACUUCCUUCUGGAGGAGAAGGUCUAGAGACCUCUGCUUCUGAAGUAGGGACUGACCUCAGUGGGCUUCCUUCUGGAAGGGAGGGUCUAGAGACUUCAGCUUCUGGAGCUGAGGACCUCAGUGGGUUGCCUUCUGGAAAAGAAGACUUGGUGGGGUCAGCUUCUGGAGACUUGGACUUGGGCAAACUGCCUUCUGGAACUCUAGGAAGUGGGCAAGCUCCAGAAACAAGUGGUCUUCCCUCUGGAUUUAGUGGUGAGUAUUCUGGGGUGGACCUUGGAAGUGGCCCACCCUCUGGCCUGCCUGACUUUAGUGGACUUCCAUCUGGAUUCCCAACUGUUUCCCUAGUGGAUUCUACAUUGGUGGAAGUGGUCACAGCCUCCACUGCAAGUGAACUGGAAGGGAGGGGAACCAUUGGCAUCAGUGGUGCAGGAGAAAUAUCUGGACUGCCCUCCAGUGAGCUGGACAUUAGUGGGAGAGCUAGUGGACUCCCUUCAGGAACUGAACUCAGUGGCCAAGCAUCUGGGUCUCCUGAUGUCAGUGGGGAAAUACCUGGACUCUUUGGUGUCAGUGGACAGCCAUCAGGGUUUCCUGACACUAGUGGGGAAACAUCUGGAGUGACUGAGCUUAGCGGGCUGUCCUCUGGACAACCAGGUAUUAGUGGAGAAGCAUCUGGAGUUCUUUAUGGCACUAGUCAACCCUUUGGCAUAACUGAUCUGAGUGGAGAAACAUCUGGGGUCCCUGAUCUCAGUGGGCAGCCUUCAGGGUUACCAGGGUUCAGUGGGGCAACAUCAGGAGUCCCUGACCUGGUUUCUGGUACCACGAGUGGCAGCGGUGAAUCUUCUGGGAUUACAUUUGUGGACACCAGUUUGGUUGAAGUGGCCCCUACUACAUUUAAAGAAGAAGAAGGCUUAGGGUCUGUGGAACUCAGUGGCCUCCCUUCCGGAGAGGCAGAUCUGUCAGGCAAAUCUGGGAUGGUGGAUGUCAGUGGACAGUUUUCUGGAACAGUCGAUUCCAGUGGGUUUACAUCCCAGACUCCGGAAUUCAGUGGCCUACCAAGUGGCAUAGCUGAGGUCAGUGGAGAAUCCUCCAGAGCUGAGAUUGGGAGCAGCCUGCCCUCGGGAGCAUAUUAUGGCAGUGGAACUCCAUCUAGUUUCCCCACUGUCUCUCUUGUAGACAGAACUUUGGUGGAAUCUGUAACCCAGGCUCCAACAGCCCAAGAGGCAGGAGAAGGGCCUUCUGGCAUUUUAGAACUCAGUGGUGCUCAUUCUGGAGCACCAGACAUGUCUGGGGAGCAUUCUGGAUUUCUGGACCUAAGUGGGCUGCAGUCCGGGCUGAUAGAGCCCAGCGGAGAGCCACCAGGUACUCCAUAUUUUAGUGGGGAUUUUGCCAGCACCACCAAUGUAAGUGGAGAAUCCUCUGUAGCCAUGGGCACCAGUGGAGAGGCCUCAGGACUUCCAGAAGUUACUUUAAUCACUUCUGAGUUCGUGGAGGGUGUUACUGAACCAACUAUUUCUCAGGAACUAGGCCAAAGGCCCCCUGUGACACACACACCCCAGCUUUUUGAGUCCAGUGGAAAAGUCUCCACAGCUGGGGACAUUAGUGGAGCUACCCCAGUGCUCCCUGGGUCUGGAGUAGAAGUAUCAUCAGUCCCAGAAUCUAGCAGUGAGACGUCCGCCUAUCCUGAAGCUGGGUUCGGGGCAUCUGCCGCCCCUGAGGCCAGCAGAGAAGAUUCUGGGUCCCCUGAUCUGAGUGAAACCACCUCUGCAUUCCACGAAGCUAACCUUGAGAGAUCCUCUGGCCUAGGAGUGAGCGGCAGCACUUUGACAUUUCAAGAAGGCGAGGCGUCCGCUGCCCCAGAAGUGAGUGGAGAAUCCACCACCACCAGUGAUGUGGGGACAGAGGCACCAGGCUUGCCUUCAGCCACUCCCACGGCUUCUGGAGACAGGACUGAAAUCAGCGGAGACCUGUCUGGUCACACCUCGCAGCUGGGCGUUGUCAUCAGCACCAGCAUCCCAGAGUCUGAGUGGACCCAGCAGACCCAGCGCCCUGCAGAGACGCAUCUAGAAAUUGAGUCCUCAAGCCUCCUGUACUCAGGAGAAGAGACUCACACAGUCGAAACAGCCACCUCCCCAACAGAUGCUUCCAUCCCAGCUUCUCCGGAAUGGAAACGUGAAUCAGAAUCAACUGCUGCAGCCCCCGCCAGGUCCUGUGCAGAGGAGCCCUGUGGAGCUGGGACCUGCAAGGAGACAGAGGGACACGUCAUAUGCCUGUGCCCCCCUGGCUACACUGGCGAGCACUGUAACAUAGACAUUGAUGAGUGCCUCUCAAGCCCUUGUCUGAAUGGAGCCACCUGCGUGGAUGCCAUCGACUCUUUCACAUGCUUAUGCCUUCCCAGCUACGAAGGGGACCUGUGUGAGAUUGACCAGGAGGUAUGUGAGGAGGGCUGGAACAAGUACCAGGGCCACUGUUACCGCCACUUCCCGGACCGCGAGACCUGGGUGGAUGCUGAGCGCCGGUGUCGGGAGCAGCAGUCACACCUGAGCAGCAUCGUCACCCCCGAGGAGCAGGAGUUUGUCAACAACAAUGCCCAAGACUACCAGUGGAUCGGCCUGAACGACAGGACCAUCGAAGGGGACUUCCGCUGGUCAGAUGGACACCCCAUGCAAUUUGAGAACUGGCGCCCCAACCAGCCUGACAACUUUUUUGCCGCUGGAGAGGACUGUGUGGUGAUGAUCUGGCACGAGAAGGGCGAGUGGAAUGAUGUUCCCUGCAAUUACCACCUCCCCUUCACGUGUAAAAAGGGCACAGUGGCCUGCGGAGAGCCCCCUGUGGUGGAGCAUGCCAGGACCUUCGGGCAGAAGAAGGACCGGUAUGAGAUCAAUUCCCUGGUGCGGUACCAGUGCACAGAGGGGUUUGUCCAGCGCCACAUGCCCACCAUCCGGUGCCAGCCCAGCGGGCACUGGGAGGAGCCUCAGAUCACCUGCACAGACCCCACCACCUACAAACGCAGACUACAGAAGCGGAGCUCACGGCACCCUCGGAGGAGCCGCCCCAGCACAGCCCACUGAGAAGAGCUUCCAGGACGCACCCAGGACGCUGAGCCCAGGAGCCUGCCAGGCUGACGUGCAUCCCACCCAGACGGUGUCCUCUUCUUGUCGCUUUUUGUCAUAUAAGGAAUCCCAUUAAAGAAGGAAAAAAAUAAAUCCCACAUUUGUGUAUGCACCCACUCACCCCUCCAAAUCAGCAAAACCGCAUCUAAUUUGUCCGCCGAAUGCCAAAGCAAAGCAAACUUAUUAUAACCCUUGGACUGAGUUUAGAGACAUUUCUUCAAUUUCCCAUCGUGCCUUUCCAGGGACCAGUGCAGGGACAGGGGGAGAAGGGGAGGGGUUAAGUUAAAUAAAGAAGAUUAUUUUUGUUUCCUGACUUUAUCCAAGAGCAGUGCAAUCGUUGGUUAUUUCACCUCCAGGGAGAGCUAGGGAGGAGGGAGGAGGGCUCCAAAGGAGCUGGAAGGAGCAGAGGCCUGAGAGCAGGAAGAACUCGGAACCGCAGCUGAAUGUAUUGGAUGAGAAGGAGCCAGGAGGGCUACACCAUCUGUAUGAGGGAAAAGCCUUGGGGGAGAGGGGUGGGUUCCUGCCUCCUGCCGAGGGUAAGCCGGCAGGAGAGAGCCAUCAGAGGGACCUCCGCUGCCUGGGAGUUGGGUUCCCUCCAAGGGUCCCUCUUUCAGUGUCCUCUCUCUCACCUGGGUCUGCCACCCUAACAGGUGGCAACUCGGCAGGGCUGCUGGGGGCACUUCCUGCCCAGUGGGGGGUGCCGCCCAACCUUCUCCCCUCCCCACCCCCGCCCCCGGGACCGUGCAGGCACCAGGGUUCCGUGCACCUAUUUAUAUUUUUGAAAACUGAAGAUUAUAAUAUUAUAAUAAUAAUAAAGACAUUGGAAGAGA